GCGGAAGUUGCCGGCGGCCGCGCGGCCUCCCGGGCGGGCCUACAGCCAUGUCCCGGGACCCGGGGUCGGGCGGCUGGGAGGAGGCCCCGCGCGCAGCUGCCGCGCUCUGCACCCUGUACCACGAGGCCGGACAGCGGCUGCGCCGCCUGCAGGACCAGCUCGCUGCCCGCGACGCCCUCAUCGCUCGCCUCCGCGCCCGCCUGGCCGCGCUGGAGGGGGACGCCGCGCCGUCCCUAGUGGACGCGCUGCUGGAGCAGGUUGCGCGCUUCCGGGAGCAGCUGCGAAGGCAGGAGGGCGGCGCCGCCGAGGCCCAGAUGCGCCAGGUACGAGGGCGGGUACCAGAGGAGCUGCGGGAGCGAGAGUGCGUGUGGCGGCCGCCGGGUCCUGGGAAAUUGAGAGGCUGACUGAGCGACUAGAAGAAAAAGAGAGGGAGAUGCAGCAGCUGCUGAGCCAGCCCCAACACGAGCGAGAGAAGGAAGUCGUCCUGCUACGGAGGAGCAUGGCAGAAGGGGAGCGCGCCCGGGCCGCCAGUGACGUCCUGUGCCGCUCCUUGGCCAACGAGACCCAUCAGCUGCGGAGGACGCUGACCGCCACCGCCCACAUGUGUCAGCAUCUGGCCAAGUGUCUGGAUGAACGACAGCAUGCACAAAGGAAUGUGGGGGAGAGAAGUCCUGACCAGUCGGAACACACAGAUGGGCACACCUCUGUCCAGAGUGUUAUUGAGAAGUUGCAGGAAGAAAAUCGACUGUUAAAACAGAAGGUGACUCACGUUGAAGACCUCAAUGCCAAGUGGCAGCGCUACAACGCCAGCAGGGACGAAUACGUGAGGGGGCUCCAUGCGCAGCUCAGGGGGCUGCAGAUCCCCCACGAGCCCGAGCUGAUGAGGAAGGAGAUCUCCCGGCUCAACAGACAGUUGGAAGAGAAAAUAAAUGACUGUGCCGAAGUGAAGCAGGAGCUGGCGGCCUCCAGGACGGCCCGGGAUGCUGCGUUGGAGCGGGUGCAGAUGCUGGAACAGCAGAUUCUCGCUUACAAGGAUGACUUCAUGUCAGAAAGGGCCGAUCGGGAACGGGCUCAAAGUAGGAUUCAAGAACUGGAGGAAAAGGUCGCCUCUUUGCUGCACCAGGUGUCCUGGAGACAGGAUUCUCGAGAGCCAGACGCCGGCCGGAUUCACGCUGGGAGCAAAACUGCCAAGUAUUUGGCCGCCGACGCAUUAGAGCUUAUGGUGCCUGGUGGCUGGAGGCCUGGGACUGGGUCCCAGCAGCCAGAACCCCCUGCAGAGGGCGGGCAUCCUGGCGCGGCCCAGAGAGGCCAGGGGGACCUUCAGUGCCCUCACUGCCUGCAGUGCUUCAGUGACGAGCAAGGGGAAGAGCUCCUCAGGCAUGUGGCUGAGUGCUGCCAGUGACCGAGACUCACCCGUGCCCUUGCGGCCUCCUGGCCCGGUGCAGCUGCCCUCAGGGACAGGGUGGGUGCUCUCAGAUGCCAUGGGUUGAGCUCUACUGAGAGCCAAGGCCCCUAGAAUAGUUGCGGGGCACUCUGAUCGUUCACUUUGGUCCCUUUGGCUAUGGAACAGGCUGGGUCACAGGGAACUGCCAGUGAGGCUGGAGGCUGGAGGUGGAGAUGGGGUCAGGAACAUCUGGCAGAGGGAGGUCCCAGUCUGUGUCUCCAUCAGGCUUAAGCCAGAGCUAUCUGGUGCUGGUGUGCCAGCCCCUCCCCCAGCCUGCCUAGAAAGGGGUGGCUGCCUGAGGGAGUCACUUGUAUGGUCCCCAGGGUGGGAGCCCCAUCCUGUUCUAUGGAAUAAAGCGUCGCCUCUCUGCCUCGAACCAGUCAAAUGGAGUAUUGCGGCUGCACGUCACACUAGGGUGGCCACCCCCGCCAUUGCGAGCCACAUGUCUGCACUGAGAAACUGCAUUUCAGUAGCAUUUGUCAUCCAGCCGGAAGUUAAAGCACACUUACUUUAUUCACCUAUUUUUAUAAUAAACGUUCUUGCUGCUGUGACUGCUCUGAGAAUUUG